ACAGAAGACUGGACACAAUUCCGAAGAGCUGCCCAGAAGGAGAGAACAAUGUCAUCACUACCCAGUGGCAGACACCUUUCACCCCAGCUACACAAGAGGGGGCAGAUGUGUGAGGAUCACUGCAGUCCAGGAGUUCGAUGUUUCAGUGAGCUGUGAUUGCACCACUGCAUAUCAGCCUGGGUGACAGAGCAAGACCCUAUCUCAAAAAUACAGAAAAAUCAUCAACCACUUGCAGUCGUCGUAGAAAUCAAUCAUUCCCUCCAGUUAUGUCCCUGACCCACAGGCUUCAUUUGUGCAAGUACUGGGGCUGUGCUGUCAGUAAUGUGUGCCGCUUCUGGGAAGGACGUCCAUUGCCCUUGAUGAUUGUGGUACCAUACACACUGCCUGUUUCCUUGCCUGUUGGUUCGUGCGUGAUAAUCACAGGGACACCGAUCCUCACUUUUGUCAAGGACCCACAGCUGGAGGUGAAUUUCUACACUGGGAUGGAUGAGGACUCAGAUAUUGCUUUCCAAUUCCGACUGCACUUUGGUCAUCCUGCAAUCAUGAACAGUUGUGUGUUUGGCAUAUGGAGAUAUGAGGAGAAAUGCUACUAUUUACCCUUUGAAGAUGGCAAACCAUUUGAGCUGUGCAUCUAUGUGCGUCACAAGGAAUACAAGGUAAUGGUAAAUGGCCAACGCAUUUACAACUUUGCCCAUCGAUUCCCGCCAGCAUCUGUGAAGAUGCUGCAAGUCUUCAGAGAUAUCUCCCUGACCAGAGUGCUUAUCAGCGAUUGAGGGAGAUGAUCAGACUCCUCAUUGUUGAGGAAUCCCUCUUUCUACCUGACCAUGGGAUUCCCAGAGCCUACUAACAGAAUAAUCCCUCCUCACCCCUUCCCCUACACUUGAUCAUUAAAACAGCACCAAAC